GGUUUCCAGCCAUGGCUGCCAUUACCUGACCAGCGCCACAGCCGGUCUCUCUGCAGGCGCCGGGAGAAGUGACCAGAGCAAUUUCUGCUUUUCACAGGGCGGGUUUCUCAACGGUGACUUGUGGGCAGUGCCUUCUGCUGAGCGAGUCAUGGCCCGAAGGCAGAACUAACUGUGCCUGCAGUCUUCACUCUCAGGAUGCAGCCGAGGUGGGCCCAAGGGGCCACGAUGUGGCUUGGAGUCCUGCUGACCCUUCUGCUCUGUUCAAGCCUUGAGGGUCAAGAAAACUCUUUCACAAUCAACAGUGUUGACAUGAAGAGCCUGCCGGACUGGACGGUGCAAAAUGGGAAGAACCUGACCCUGCAGUGCUUCGCGGAUGUCAGCACCACCUCUCACGUCAAGCCUCAGCACCAGAUGCUGUUCUAUAAGGAUGACGUGCUGUUUUACAACAUCUCCUCCAUGAAGAGCACAGAGAGUUAUUUUAUUCCUGAAGUCCGGAUCUAUGACUCAGGGACAUAUAAAUGUACUGUGAUUGUGAACAACAAAGAGAAAACCACUGCAGAGUACCAGGUGUUGGUGGAAGGAGUGCCCAGUCCCAGGGUGACACUGGACAAGAAAGAGGCCAUCCAAGGUGGGAUCGUGAGGGUCAACUGUUCUGUCCCAGAGGAAAAGGCCCCAAUACACUUCACAAUUGAAAAACUUGAACUAAAUGAAAAAAUGGUCAAGCUGAAAAGAGAGAAGAAUUCUCGAGACCAGAAUUUUGUGAUACUGGAAUUCCCCGUUGAGGAACAGGACCGCGUUUUAUCCUUCCGAUGUCAAGCUAGGAUCAUUUCUGGGAUCCAUAUGCAGACCUCAGAAUCUACCAAGAGUGAACUGGUCACCGUGACGGAAUCCUUCUCUACACCCAAGUUCCACAUCAGCCCCACCGGAAUGAUCAUGGAAGGAGCUCAGCUCCACAUUAAGUGCACCAUUCAAGUGACUCACCUGGCCCAGGAGUUUCCAGAAAUCAUAAUUCAGAAGGACAAGGCGAUUGUGGCCCACAACAGACAUGGCAACAAGGCUGUGUACUCAGUCAUGGCCAUGGUGGAGCACAGUGGCAACUACACGUGCAAAGUGGAGUCCAGCCGCAUAUCCAAGGUCAGCAGCAUCGUGGUCAACAUAACAGAACUAUUUUCCAAGCCCGAACUGGAAUCUUCCUUCACACAUCUGGACCAAGGUGAAAGACUGAACCUGUCCUGCUCCAUCCCAGGAGCACCUCCAGCCAACUUCACCAUCCAGAAGGAAGAUACGAUUGUGUCACAGACUCAAGAUUUCACCAAGAUAGCCUCAAAGUCGGACAGUGGGACGUAUAUCUGCACUGCAGGUAUUGACAAAGUGGUCAAGAAAAGCAACACAGUCCAGAUAGUCGUAUGUGAAAUGCUCUCCCAGCCCAGGAUUUCUUAUGAUGCCCAGUUUGAGGUCAUAAAAGGACAGACCAUCGAAGUCCGUUGCGAAUCGAUCAGUGGAACUUUGCCUAUUUCUUACCAACUUUUAAAAACAAGUAAAGUUUUGGAGAAUAGUACCAAGAACUCAAAUGAUCCUGCGGUAUUCAAAGACAACCCCACUGAAGACGUCGAAUACCAGUGUGUUGCAGAUAAUUGCCAUUCCCAUGCCAAAAUGUUAAGUGAGGUUCUGAGGGUGAAGGUGAUAGCCCCGGUGGAUGAGGUCCAGAUUUCUAUCCUGUCAAGUAAGGUGGUGGAGUCUGGAGAGGACAUUGUGCUGCAAUGUGCUGUGAAUGAAGGAUCUGGUCCCAUCACCUAUAAGUUUUACAGAGAAAAAGAGGGCAAACCCUUCUAUCAAAUGACCUCAAAUGCCACCCAGGCAUUUUGGACCAAGCAGAAGGCUAGCAAGGAACAGGAGGGAGAGUAUUACUGCACAGCCUUCAACAGAGCCAACCACGCCUCCAGUGUCCCCAGAAGCAAAAUACUGACAGUCAGAGUCAUUCUUGCCCCAUGGAAGAAAGGACUUAUUGCAGUGGUUAUCAUCGGAGUGAUCAUUGCUCUCUUGAUCAUUGCGGCCAAAUGUUAUUUUCUGAGGAAAGCCAAGGCCAAGCAGAUGCCAGUGGAAAUGUCCAGGCCAGCAGUACCACUUCUGAACUCCAACAACGAGAAAAUGUCAGAUCCCAAUAUGGAAGCUAACAGUCAUUACGGUCACAAUGACGAUGUCAGAAACCAUGCAAUGAAACCAAUAAAUGAUAAUAAAGAGCCUCUGAACUCAGACGUGCAGUACACGGAAGUUCAAGUGUCCUCAGCUGAGUCUCACAAAGAUCUAGGAAAGAAGGACACAGAGACAGUGUACAGUGAAGUCCGGAAAGCUGUCCCUGAUGCCGUGGAAAGCAGAUACUCUAGAACGGAAGGCUCCCUUGAUGGAACUUAGACAGCAAGGCCAGAUGCACAUCCCUGGAAGGACAUCCAUGUUCCGAGAAGAACAGAUAAUCCCUGUAUUUCAAGACCUCUGUGCACUUAUUUAUGAACCUGCCCUGCUCCCACAGAACACAGCAAUUCCUCAGGCUAAGCUGCCGGUUCUUAAAUCCAUCCUGCUAAGUUAAUGUUGGGUAGAAAGAGAUACAGAGGGGCUGUUGAAUUUCCCACAUACCCUCCUUCCACCAAGUUGGAACAUCCUUGGAAAUUGGAAGAGCACAAGAGGAGAUCCAGGGCAAGGCCAUUGGGAUAUUCUGAAACUUGAAUAUUUUGUUUUGUGCAGAGAUAAAGACCUUUUCCAUGCACCCUCAUACACAGAAACCAAUUUUCUUUUUUAUACUCAAUCAUUUCUAGCGCAUGGCCUGGUUAGAGGCUGGUUUUUUCUCUUUUCCUUUGGUCCUUCAAAGGCUUGUAGUUUUGGCUAGUCCUUGUUCUUUGGAAAUACACAGUGCUGACCAGACAGCCUCCCCCUGUCCCCUCUAUGACCUCGCCCUCCACAAAUGGGAAAACCAGACUACUUGGGAGCACCGCCUGUGAAAUACCAACCUGAAGACACCGUUCAUUCAGGCAACGCACAAAACAGAAAAUGAAGGUGGAACAAGCACAGAUGUUCUUCAACUGUUUUUGUCUACACUCUUUCUCUUUUCCUCUACCAUGCUGAAGGCUGAAAGACAGGAAGAUGGUGCCAUCAGCAAAUAUUAUUCUUAAUUGAAAACUUGAAAUGUGUAUGUUUCUUACUAAUUUUUAAAAAUGUAUUCCUUGCCAGGGCAGGCAAGGUGGCUCACGCCUGUAAUCCCAGCACUUCAGGAGGCUGAGGUGGGCGGAUCACCUGAGGUCAGGAGUUUGAGACCAGCCUGAUGAAACCCUGUCUCUACUAAAAAUACAAGAAUUAGCCGGGCGUGGUGGCGCAUGCCUGUAGUAUCAGCUACUCAAGAGGCUGAGGUGAGAUUAUCGCUUGAACCCAGGAAACGGAGGUUGUAGUGAGCGGAGAUCGCGCCACUGCACUCCAGCCUGAGUGACAGAGUGAGAAUCCAUCUCAAAAAAAACAAAAAACAAAAUUGCUUGCUAAAGAAGUGGUCUCCUGAGGUCUUAAGACAUUCCUGACAGUGUCUUGAGUGGGUGGGAGAGAGGCUGCUGUCAUUGCGCUGUGGAAUUUCACAGAUGAGAACCACGCCUAGCCAAAAUCACUUUUCCUGUUUGCCUCAGUGACACAGCUGCAGGGACCCUCGUGGAUGUUGUAUUAAAUAAAUUUGACCUUUGCUCUUUGCAGAUCUGUGAAAUGUUGUCUUCUGAGGGGCCACAUGCAUCUAUAGUGCUGAGGACUCCUUGGGCCUCUGAAGUCACAGAGAGAACCGAGCAGGUCUAUGUUUUUGUUUUGUUGUUUUGAGACGGAGAUUCGCUCUUGUUGCCCGGGCUGGACUGCAGCGGCGCAACCUCUGCUCACUGCAACCUCCGCCUCCUGGGUUCAAGCAGUUCUCCUGUCUCAGCCUCCCGAGUAGCUGGGAUUACAGGCACAUGUCACCACGCCUGGCUAAUUUUUGUAUUUUUAGUAGAGAUGGGGUUUCACCACGUUGGCCAGGCUGAUCUCGAAUGCCUGACCUUUGGUGAUCUGCCCGCCUUGUCCUCAUGUGUGCUCCACAGGCCUUUGGGUUGGGAUUGCAGGCGUGAGCCACCAUGCCCAGCCUAGACUCUUUUGACAAUAUGAUGAAAGCUGUUGGUUCCUUUCCCCAACACACACACACCGAGUUGUAUCACGAAAAUGUCAUACAAUUUCCAGGUUUUCUGAGUGGUGGGCUCAGAUUGAGGUCAAAGGAUCAGACGACCUCUAACGACCUUCAUGUCUCUGUUGAUGAUCUGGGGACAGCCAGAUCCCCUGUGUCCAGGGAGUUCCUUAGUCCCUUGCCACCACCAGAGAAGGGCAAUUGCCACGGGAGCUGCAAAGACCCUAUUCCUACUCCUGGUGCCUUACUUAUGCAGCACGACUGAAUUUUUUGUUUUGUUUUGUUUUGUUGAGACAGGGGCUUGCUCUGUUGCCCAGGCUGGAGUGCAGUGGCACAACAAUGGCUCACCGCAGCCUCGAACCCCUGGGCUCAAGCGAUCCUCCCAUCUCAGCUUCCUGGGUAGCUGGGACCAGAGGCGUGAGCCGCCAUAGCUGGCUAAUUUUUAAUUUUUUUUUUGCAGAGAUGAGGUUUCACCAUGGUGCCCAGGCUGGUCUCGAACUUCUGGGCUCAAGUGAUCCUCCCUCCUUGGCCUCGCAAAGUGCUGGGAUUGCAGGCAUGAGCCACCGCCCCCGGCCUGUGGAGCACACAUGAGUUUAAAAUUACUUUCCCUUCUGCCUAUAUUUCCGAGGAGGAAACUUCAUGCGCAGGGAUCUUUCUUAGUGGAUUUAAUGGCUAAAAGGUCUGUCUGAAUCCAGGACGCUGGCUUUAGCCUUCCUCGGCAGCUGCCGUAACCCCGGUGUCUAAACCUGAAGCAUCCCAGGAGCACCCACUCCAGGAGUUUUCUCGGCCGCGGAACUCAUUAGUUAGAGCGCCCUCUUGUGUUCUCAUGUGGUAAUCGGUCACUGAAGGACUUAAAAUGGUCCUUAGCCAACACACAGUAAAACUUUUCCCUCUUCUGACCCCAAGAGGUCAGCCACCCAUUUCAUGAGCAUAUACUGGUCGCCCCAUCAGCGUUCUCUGAUUGGCUAACUGAACCCACUCCCCGACCUAGACUCAAGACAGGCGAAGUGACGCUUAGGUCAACAUUCACUCACUAAAGCAACGACUGUCGGGCGAUUUUGUCUCCCGCUGGUUUUGGAAUGGUGUCUGGAGACAUUUUUGGUUGUCACAGCUGGGUGGGUGUGCUCCCGGCAUCUGGUGGGUAGAAACCAAGCAUGCUCCUAAACAUCCUACAGGCACAGAACCGUCUCCCACGACCAAGCAUGAUCAAGUCCCAAAUGCCAAUAAUGGCCAGGUUGAGAAACUCUGCACAGAAGCAUCCAGUUAUUUGUCUGUUUGCUCAACAAGCUUGUGCUCAUCAUGCUCUGUGUUCCUGACGCUGUGCUGGGUGUUGGCGGUGGGAAGAUUACAAGAGUCACAUGGCAGCUGUCCUCCUGGAAGGUACAACCCAGUAGAGAUGCAGACUAACAGAGAGCCAAUUACAAAGCAGUGUGACAAGCGUCAUGGUGGAAAAUUAAAAGCUCAAACAAGGGCACAUGGGAGGGGCUUCCAACACAGACUUUGGGGGAUCCAGGAAGGUCUAAGAGGAAAGUGGGUCUCACCAAAGCCUUGACCAUAGGCAGAGGGUACCAGUGGAAAAGGUGGGGUGAAGAACAUUGAGGACAAAAGGAAGAAGUGCAGGAAGGCCCUGAGGCAAGGGAGUGGGGGGUGCCCUGGAGGGAUGGCAGCAGGGCAGUCUGUCAGACCCAAGUGGCCUCCAGCCCUAGAAGCCAAUUAGUCCUCCUCAAAAAGCUGUCACUGUCCCCUAAGAAUUGCUGCCAGGCUCCCACUGGCCUGACUCAGUCUUUGAGAGUCUUAAGGAGGAGGUCUCUGAAAGGUACACACCAAGAACUCUCCCCAGCACAGCUGUUUUUAAGACUCUCCACCAGCGUCAUUGGCGUGUUGGGAAGAAACCCUCUGCCACAGAGGCCAGCUUCAGCCUUUGCCUAACACCGCAAGGGCAAAUGGAAAGGUAAACGGGAAGGAGAUGUCUCCCCAGCAGGCUAUUUGAGGACAGUCUUCCCUGCAGAAGAUCUCAACCUGGGGUCCACAGAGUGGAAAUGUUAGAGUAGGGAGCUAGGCAAACAUGAGCAGGACAGGUGAGGGCCCCCACAGGAAUGUCAGGCUACCAUCAGGUGAUGGUCAGGUGGUUGUUAAACUGUCUCUGUAAAAUAAUAAUUGGUUGCAGCCAGCUCCAAGCAAGGACAGUCUCUCAAUAGAUACAAAACACCCUGAUCUGGUGAUCAGCCGCUUCCCGAUAAGAUCUCAGGAGCUGGGCAAGCAGCCUGGAGCAUGCGCACCAAGAGGCAAAAUGGCGGAAUUUAACCAGUAUAUGACCUACCUUCCUCUGGGAACGCACGACUGGUAAGGGGAAAAAUGCCUCAAGUGAGCAUGCGCGCAACUUCAGUAAUCACACUGUGCAUGCGACCCCUUCCAAGUGCUGGCAGGUCACCACAUACGCGGACAGCCUGCUGCAAGGGAAGAAUCAGGGGAGAUGAGACGUAAAUCCCAGAACUAUGCCAAAUACAUAAAACCCCAAGUUAAGGGUCAGGCAGGGCACUUAGAUCUCUCAAGUUGCCUGCCUGACCCAAGUGUAGUGUACUUCCUUUUGUUCCUGCUCUAAAACUUUUUAAUAAACUCUCACUCCUGCUCUAAAA